GCAGCUCACUUCCGGACCGCGGAUAGCACUGGCGACCCUAGCGGGUGAGAGGCCCUUCAGGGCCGCGGCGGGUGAGAGCCUCUUCAGGGCCGCAGCGGGUGGCGGGCGAAGUGGUAAACGGGCGCGGGGACGGGUUUUGGUGCCGCUACGGGGCUCGGCGGCAGCGGGGUUGCAGUAGAGCCCGUCUCCCUCCGCUCAGCCCCGGCUGAGGGCGGCAAGUCUCUCAGGAGCUGCCUUCAGCGGCCCCGAGGCCCUGCGGGUCUGGACGCUGAGGGGCCGCCGCGCUGUAGGCUCAGGAUCUCCUUCCCCUGGUGCUUUGGACUUCCAAGUCUGUCUUCCCAGUCUAGGUCUUCCGCAUAAUCCACUUGGAGGUUGAGCGCACCAUCACAUCUAAGCCAUCAGCAAGUUUGUUGGUUUUAAUCUCCAAAAUACGUCUUGAUUUUGUCUGACUCUUUGCCACCACCCUGAUCUAAGCCCUUAUCAUCUGCUUGAAUCACUAACUUGUCUCCACUUGCAGUUUUUAAAAGAGUUGCUUCCAUUUGACUUUUUCUGUCUGCUGUACCAGCAUAUGAGUUUCAGGAGGGGUCAUUGAUGCAGUCAUUCUCAGUCUCCUCGGAGGGAGUCUGAAGAUGCUUAAAGAGCAUCCAGAGAUGGCGGAAGCUCCUCAGCAGCAGUUGGGUAUUCCUGUGGUGAAACUGGAGAAAGAGUUGCCAUGGGGCAGAGGAAGGGAGGACCCUAGUCCAGAGACUUUUCGGCUGAGGUUUCGGCAGUUCCGCUACCAGGAGGCAGCUGGACCCCAGGAAGCUCUUAGGGAGCUCCAGGAGCUCUGUCGUCGGUGGCUGAGGCCCGAGUUGCACACCAAGGAGCAGAUCCUGGAGCUGCUGGUGCUGGAGCAGUUCCUCACUAUCCUGCCCCGCGAGUUCUACGCCUGGAUCCGGGAGCAUGGCCCAGAGAGUGGCAAGGCCCUGGCCGCCAUGGUGGAGGACCUGACAGAAAGAGCACUGGAGGCCAAGGCGGUUCCAUGCCACAGGCAGGGAGAGCAGGAGGAAACAGCACUUUGCAGAGGCGCUUGGGAGCCAGGCAUCCAGCUGGGGCCAGUGGAGGUCAAGCCUGAAUGGGGGAUGCCCCCUGGGGAAGGAGUUCAAGGUCCAGACCCAGGUACCGAGGAGCAGCUCAGUCAGGACCCUGGAGAUGAGACACGGGCCUUCCAGGAGCAAGCACUACCUGUUCUGCAGGCGGGUCCUGGCCUCCCCGCAGUGAAUCCCAGAGACCAAGAGAUGGCAGCUGGGUUCUUUACUGCUGGAUCGCAGGGGUUGGGGCCAUUUAAAGAUAUGGCCCUGGCCUUCCCUGAGGAGGAGUGGAGGCAUGUGACCCCAGCCCAGAUAGACUGCUUUGGGGAGUAUGUGGAACCGCAGGACUGCAGGGUCUCUCCAGAAUGGCUUCCACAAUGUCUUAAAAAGAAAACCCUAAAAAACAAAAAUUAUGGAUGAAGGAAGAUUGUUCAAUGAAAAGUGGACAAAUGACUUUUUCUUGUUGAGGCAAAUAGCGAAGCACUCUGCUUAAUUUCCACGGAAUUUGUGCCAGUUUUCAAAGACUACAAUUUGAAGAGGCAUUAUAUGCAAAAACGUGCUGACAAAUUUGGUGUGUAUGUGUUGUAAGGACAAAAUAGCAGAACUGAAAAAAAGUCUGUCUUUUCAACAAAAAAGAUUUUUUAAAAAGUUACAACUCGGACUCAAUCGUAAGGUAAAACCUAGUUAUGUGGUAGCAAAUUUAAUAGCAAAAAAAUCAAAACCAUUUACUGAUGGUGAGUUUAUUAAGCAAUGUCUGGAAGAUGUGGUAGAUAUUAUUUGCCUUGAGAAACUGAUAUUUCUAAAAUCAGUUUGUCUCACCAGACUAUAGCCAGGAGAAUUGGAGAAAUUGGGAAAUCUAUUGAAAGACGUUUGGAGAGUAAAACUGCUAAUUUAAAAUUUUAUGCUUUGGUGAUGGAUGAAGGCACUGACACUACAGAUACGGCACAACUUGCUAUUUUUAUUAGAGGUAUUGAUGAUGAAUAUAAUGUCACUGAAGAAAUCGAAAUGUCACCAUGCUAUUAAAAGACACAACUAAAUCAAGAGAUUUAUAUGAAGCAGUGAAAAAUAUGUUAAAGCAAUUUUCUUUGUCCUUUGUAAACAUAUGUGAUAUAGCUACAGAUGCUGCCCUGGCGAUGGUAGGUAAAAGAGAGGGACUUGUACAAUUAAUAGAUGAUGCAGUUGCCACACAAAACUCACAUUUGAUGAAGUAUUAUUGCAUAAUACAUCAAGAAAAUCCAUGUGCACAAGCUUUAAAAGUAGAUAACGUCAUGCAAAUUGUCAUCAAGGCUGUAAAUUUCACAAGGGCCCAGGAAUUGAAUCAUCGCUAGUUUCAGGAAUUCCUUAAAAGUAUGGAUGCUGACUCUAGCAAGUCAUUCACUUUUUAGAAGUAAGAUGGUUAAGUCAAGGCAAAAUGUAAAGAUUUUAUGCUUUGUGAUGUGAAAUCAAGCUGUUUAUGGUAUCAAACAAAAUUGGUGCCAGAACUUGACAAUGAAAACUGGCUUACAGAUUUAGCAUUUUUAGUGGGUUUGACGGCCCAUUUAAGUGAGUUAAACCUGUGUCUUCAAGUUGAAAACCAACUUAACAAUACAAUGUUUCAAACCAUAACAGCAUUCCAUAUGAAACUGAAAUUAUGGCAAGCUCAAAUUAAGGCAAACAAUUUUAUGCAUUUCGACAUGUUGGCUAAACAUGGUCCUGUGAACAGCCAAAAAUACGCAGCCUUGCUUUUCAAUUUGAUACAGGAAUUUGAAAACAGGUAUUUCAAGAUUUCUGAAAAAAUCAUCAAUAUUUUGGUAUAUUUGCAACUCCAUUUUCAGUCGACAUAUAUAUGUUACCUGGCAAUUUUGAAAUGGAAUGCCUAGAGCUGCAAUCUGAUGUUCAACUUAUAGAAAAAUUUGAUUUUGCCUCUUUACUGGACUUUUGUAAGACCUGUCUUCCCAAUGACAAAUAUCCCUUGCUUCACAAUCACACCUUGUUCAUGUCAUUGCUUUUUGGCAGCACUUACAUUUGUGAGCUACUAUUUUCAAGGAUGAAGAACACGAAGAGUAAAAUUAGAACCAAAAUAUCUGAUGAGCACCUUGAGAACUCACUGAGAAUUGCAACUACUUCCAUCAAGCCAGAUACUGAUGGAUUAGUUUCUCAAAAACAAUGUCAAGUACCCCACUAGUUUUAUGUUGUUCUCUUUUCUUUUAUAAUAAAAAAUAUCAAAAAAGUAGUGAAGUUUAGCUAGAUAUGUACAUUUUCUGUAUCAGUGAUUGCAAACUUGGAACCUGUUCAAUGAUUUUGAAAGACCCUCUGAAUGGGGCAGUGCAUAAUUAGGAUUAUUAUGCAAGGACAUUUUUGCUUAUCUGUGGUGGUAGAUAUAUAAUGAAAACUAUACACAGACCAUUUGUGUGUGUGUGUGUGUGUGUGUGUGUGUGUGUGUGUGUGUGUGUGUAUUUUAUGUGUGGCCCACGACACUUCUUCUUCCACUGUGGCCCAGGGAAGCCAAAAGAUUGGACACCUCUGCUUUAAUUCUUAUCAAAAUUAUGGCAGGUUUGUUUGUAGACACUUACAAGCUUAUUCUGAAUUUUUAUGGAAAGGCAAGGGACAAGAAAAGCUAAAGCCAUUCUGAAAAUAUAAAUCAAUAAAGUGGAAAGAAUUGCCCUAUAUGAUGUUAAGAGUUACUGUACAGCUACUAGAGUCACCACAGUGUGGUAUUAGUGGAGGAGUAAACAAUAAGAAAUAGAUUCACAAAAUAUACUCAGCUGAGUUUUGACAAUAUGCCUACCUUUCCAAAAUGGUGUUGGAACAUUUGGACAGCCAUAGUCCACAGAAAAUGAACCUUGAUCUAAAUCUCAUAACUUAUGCAAAUAUUAACACAAAAUGGGUAAUAGAGUUACAUUUUGUAAAGUGUUAAACUAUAUAACUCUUAGAAAAAGCAAUGUAGGAAGGAGGGCUAAGCAAAGGAUUUUCAGACUUAACACCAAAAGAACAAUCCAUAAAAGGAAAUAUUAAUACAUUGGCCUCCUCAAAUAAAUAAAAGUUUGCUCUGAUAUAGAACCUGUCAGAGAAAAAGACAAACUCCAUGUUGUGACUGUAGGACAGCAGGAGGGAGCCACAUGGUGACGGAAUGGGUCUGCAUCUUGAUGGUGCUGGUCGUUGCACAAAUCUACGAAUGUGAAAAAUUGCUUAGAACUACCCACACACAUAAACACACACAAACAAGGGCAUGUAAAACUGGUGAAAUCUGAAAAGCUCUGUAAACUAUAUCAAAGUCAAUUUCCUGUACUAUAGUAUUAGGUUGGUGCAAAAGUUAUUGCAGUUUGCCGGUUUUUGUUGUUGUUGUUGUUGUUGUUGUUUGAGAUGGAGUCUCAUUGGGUUGCCCAGACUGGAGUAUAAUGGCGUGAUCUCGGCUCACUGCAACCUCCGCCUCCCAGGUUCAAGCGAUUCUCCUGUCUCAGACUACUGAGUAGCUGGGACUACAGGCGCAUGCCACCACACGCAGCUAAUUUUUGUAUUUUUAGUAGAGAUGGGGUUUCACCAUGUUGGUCAGGCUGAUCUCGAACUCCUGACCUCGUGAUCCACCUGCCUCGGCCUCCCAAAGUGCUGGGAUUACAGGCAUGAGCCAUUAUGCCCAGCCUGUAGUUUGCCAUUUUAACUUUUGUGCCAACCUGAUAAUAUGAAUAUACUAGAUAUAUAUUGCAAUAUACAAGAUUGCAAGAUGUUACCACUGGGCGGGACAGGAUGAAGAGUACAUGGAACCUUCCUGUACAUUUUUUAGGUAACCUUCUGUGAAUAUAUGUUUUUUUCAAAAUAAAAAUUUAAUCAGUGGA